AGAGCUGGGAAGGAGGCUCUAGAUGGCGGCUGUGCCUUAGAGAGAGCGCGCUCUGCUCCCUGCCUUUGCCUCACUUUACGCAACUUUCCCUAACUUUCGGGCAGCCUCAGGGGGCCCCCGUAGCCCCCUGCCUUUCCUAGGGACUUACUGGGGUCGAUUCGAACCUUUUUUUGGGAGAAAAGCAGCUUUUAGGAGCUUUCUUUUCGUGCCUUGUUGGAAAGAAGCAGCCGUACUGAGAGCCCAGGUCGUUGUUUUUUCCAGCUUAGAAGCCAUGGCGCACCUCCAUUUUUGUGCGCUCUCCUAAUGAGGUUUUUUUUCUUUCGGACCUGUUUUAGUAUUAAUUAUUGCUUUAUUUUUUUGACCAGUUAACAUAUUUGAGGGUUAUUUUAUUUAUUUUUCGUUUUUUAACGGAGGAUUUUGCCUUUAUUUUUAAUUAUUUGGGAUCUGAUAUUUUUCUACUAGUAGAUAGGACUCUUGGUUUGGACAUACUACAUGGAUCAGUAAAUACCUGGGCACAGGACUUCAAAGCAAACACAGAUUCCCCCUCCCCCUUAAUAUUUAAGAAUUAAAAGAUGAUGAGAAAUAAGGACAAAAGCCAAGAGGAGGACAGUUCGCUACACAGCAAUGCAUCGAGUCACUCAGCCUCUGAAGAAGCUUCGGGUUCAGACUCAGGCAGUCAGUCGGAAAGUGAGCAGGGAAGUGAUCCAGGAAGUGGACAUGGCAGCGAGUCGAACAGCAGCUCUGAAUCUUCUGAGAGUCAGUCGGAAUCUGAGAGCGAAUCAGCAGGUUCCAAAUCCCAGCCAGUCCUCCCAGAAGCCAAAGAGAAGCCAGCCUCUAAGAAGGAACGGAUAGCUGAUGUGAAGAAGAUGUGGGAAGAAUAUCCUGAUGUUUAUGGGGUCAGGCGGUCAAACCGAAGCAGACAAGAACCAUCGCGAUUUAAUAUUAAGGAAGAGGCAAGUAGCGGGUCUGAGAGUGGGAGCCCAAAAAGAAGAGGCCAGAGGCAGCUGAAAAAACAAGAAAAAUGGAAACAGGAACCCUCAGAAGAUGAACAGGAACAAGGCACCAGUGCAGAGAGUGAGCCAGAACAAAAAAAAGUAAAAGCCAGAAGACCUGUCCCCAGAAGAACAGUGCCCAAACCUCGUGUUAAAAAGCAGCCGAAGACUCAGCGUGGAAAGAGAAAAAAGCAAGAUUCUUCUGAUGAGGAUGAUGAUGAUGACGAAGCUCCCAAAAGGCAGACUCGUCGAAGAGCGGCUAAAAACGUUAGUUACAAAGAAGAUGAUGACUUUGAGACUGACUCAGAUGAUCUCAUUGAAAUGACUGGAGAAGGAGUUGAUGAACAGCAAGAUAAUAGUGAAACUAUUGAAAAGGUCUUAGAUUCAAGACUGGGAAAGAAAGGAGCCACUGGAGCAUCUACUACUGUAUAUGCGAUUGAAGCUAAUGGCGACCCUAGUGGUGACUUUGACACUGAAAAGGAUGAAGGUGAAAUCCAGUACCUCAUCAAGUGGAAGGGUUGGUCUUACAUCCACAGCACAUGGGAGAGUGAAGAAUCCUUACAGCAACAGAAAGUGAAGGGCCUAAAAAAACUAGAGAACUUCAAGAAAAAAGAGGACGAAAUCAAACAAUGGUUAGGGAAAGUUUCUCCUGAAGAUGUAGAAUAUUUCAAUUGCCAACAGGAGCUGGCUUCAGAGUUGAAUAAACAGUAUCAGAUAGUAGAAAGAGUAAUAGCUGUGAAGACAAGUAAAUCUACAUUGGGUCAAACAGAUUUUCCAGCUCAUAGUCGGAAGCCGGCACCCUCAAAUGAGCCCGAAUAUCUAUGUAAAUGGAUGGGACUCCCCUAUUCAGAGUGUAGCUGGGAAGAUGAAGCCCUCAUUGGAAAGAAAUUCCAGAAUUGCAUUGACAGCUUCCACAGUAGGAACAACUCAAAAACCAUCCCAACAAGAGAAUGCAAGGCCCUGAAGCAGAGACCACGAUUUGUAGCUUUAAAGAAACAACCUGCAUAUUUAGGAGGGGAGAAUCUGGAACUUCGAGAUUAUCAGCUAGAAGGUCUAAACUGGCUAGCUCAUUCCUGGUGCAAAAAUAAUAGUGUAAUCCUUGCUGAUGAAAUGGGCCUAGGAAAGACCAUCCAGACCAUAUCAUUCCUCUCCUACCUGUUCCACCAACACCAGCUGUAUGGCCCCUUUCUUAUAGUCGUCCCUUUAUCCACCCUCACCUCAUGGCAGAGAGAGUUUGAAAUCUGGGCACCAGAGAUUAACGUAGUGGUUUACAUAGGUGACCUGAUGAGCAGAAAUACGAUACGGGAAUAUGAAUGGAUUCAUUCCCAAACCAAAAGAUUGAAGUUCAACGCACUUAUAACAACAUAUGAGAUCCUCUUGAAAGAUAAGACUGUGCUGGGCAGUAUUAACUGGGCCUUUCUGGGAGUGGAUGAAGCCCAUCGGUUGAAGAAUGAUGACUCUUUAUUGUAUAAAACUCUGAUUGAUUUCAAGUCCAACCAUAGGCUCCUGAUUACGGGGACCCCUCUUCAGAAUUCCCUCAAAGAGCUCUGGUCCUUGCUGCACUUUAUUAUGCCGGAGAAGUUUGAAUUUUGGGAAGAUUUUGAAGAAGACCAUGGGAAGGGGAGAGAAAAUGGCUACCAGAGUCUUCAUAAGGUGCUAGAGCCUUUCCUUCUCCGGAGAGUCAAAAAAGAUGUGGAGAAAUCCCUUCCUGCUAAAGUGGAACAGAUUCUCAGGGUGGAGAUGUCAGCCCUUCAGAAACAGUAUUACAAGUGGAUUCUGACCAGGAAUUACAAGGCUCUUGCCAAAGGAACAAGAGGCAGCACAUCUGGUUUUCUUAAUAUUGUGAUGGAACUGAAAAAAUGUUGCAACCACUGCUAUCUGAUUAAACCCCCUGAAGAAAAUGAAAGGGAAAAUGGACAGGAGAUUCUUCUGUCCCUCAUAAGGAGCAGUGGGAAGUUGAUUUUAUUAGACAAACUGUUGACAAGACUUCGAGAAAGGGGGAAUCGAGUGCUUAUCUUCUCUCAGAUGGUGAGAAUGUUGGAUAUCCUGGCUGAAUACCUAACUAUUAAACACUAUCCUUUCCAGCGUCUGGAUGGUUCCAUCAAGGGAGAAAUCCGAAAACAGGCACUGGACCACUUCAAUGCAGAUGGGUCUGAGGACUUCUGUUUCCUGCUCUCGACAAGGGCUGGUGGCCUGGGAAUCAAUUUGGCUUCAGCGGACACAGUCGUCAUCUUUGACUCUGACUGGAACCCCCAGAAUGACUUGCAGGCACAAGCCCGAGCGCAUAGAAUUGGUCAAAAGAAGCAGGUAAAUAUUUACCGCUUAGUUACAAAGGGGACUGUGGAGGAGGAGAUCAUAGAACGGGCCAAAAAGAAGAUGGUAUUAGAUCAUCUGGUGAUUCAGCGCAUGGACACCACUGGCCGGACGAUCCUGGAAAACAACUCAGGAAGGUCCAACUCAAAUCCUUUUAAUAAAGAAGAGCUGACAGCUAUUUUGAAAUUUGGAGCAGAGGAUCUCUUCAAAGAACUGGAAGGGGAGGAAUCAGAACCUCAGGAAAUGGAUAUAGAUGAAAUUUUGCGGUUGGCUGAAACGAGAGAGAAUGAAGUGUCAACAAGUGCAACAGAUGAACUUCUAUCACAGUUUAAGGUUGCCAACUUUGCAACAAUGGAAGAUGAAGAAGAGCUAGAAGAGCGUCCUCACAAGGACUGGGAUGAGAUCAUUCCAGAGGAACAAAGGAAAAAAGUAGAGGAGGAAGAGCGGCAGAAGGAGCUAGAAGAAAUUUAUAUGCUGCCUCGAAUUCGGAGUUCCACUAAAAAGGCUCAGACAAAUGACAGUGACUCUGACACUGAGUCUAAGAGGCAGGCCCAGAGAUCCUCUGCUUCUGAGAGUGAAACGGAAGACUCUGAUGAUGACAAGAAGCCAAAGCGCAGAGGGCGUCCGAGGAGUGUGCGGAAGGACCUCGUGGAGGGAUUUACUGAUGCAGAGAUCCGAAGGUUCAUCAAGGCUUAUAAGAAGUUUGGUCUCCCUCUUGAACGGCUGGAGUGCAUAGCACGUGAUGCUGAGCUGGUAGAUAAGUCGGUGGCAGAUCUGAAGCGCCUGGGUGAACUGAUCCACAACAGCUGUGUGUCAGCAAUGCAGGAAUACGAAGAGCAGCUGAAAGAAAAUGCCAGCGAGGGAAAAGGACCAGGGAAAAGGAGAGGUCCAACAAUCAAGAUAUCCGGAGUUCAGGUUAAUGUGAAAUCCAUUAUCCAACAUGAAGAGGAGUUUGAGAUGCUGCAUAAAUCUAUCCCUGUGGACCCUGAAGAAAAAAAAAAAUACUGCUUAACCUGUCGUGUCAAAGCUGCACAUUUUGAUGUAGAGUGGGGGGUGGAAGAUGAUUCUCGCCUGUUGCUGGGGAUUUAUGAACAUGGCUAUGGAAACUGGGAGUUAAUUAAAACAGACCCAGAGCUUAAAUUAACUGACAAAAUUCUGCCGGUGGAGACAGAUAAAAAGCCUCAGGGGAAGCAGCUACAGACCCGAGCGGAUUACUUGUUGAAGCUGCUCAGAAAGGGUCUGGAGAAGAAGGGGGCUGUGACAGGUGGGGAAGAGGCCAAAUUAAAGAAGCGGAAGCCUCGGGUAAAGAAGGAAAACAAAGUGCCCAGGCUGAAAGAGGAGCAUGGAAUUGAGCUUUCAUCUCCUAGGCAUUCAGAUAAUCCAUCAGAAGAGGGAGAAGUGAAAGAUGAUGGCUUGGAAAAAAGUCCAAUGAAAAAAAAACAGAAGAAGAAAGAGAACAAGGAGAACAAGGAGAAACAAAUGAGUUCUAGGAAAGACAAAGAAGGGGACAAGGAAAGAAAGAAGUCAAAAGAUAAGAAAGAGAAGCCUAAAAGUGGUGAUGCCAAAUCUUCGAGUAAAUCAAAGCGAUCUCAGGGUCCUGUCCAUAUUACAGCAGGAAGUGAACCUGUCCCCAUUGGAGAGGAUGAGGAUGAUGAUCUGGACCAGGAGACAUUCAGCAUAUGUAAGGAGAGGAUGAGGCCCGUGAAAAAGGCACUGAAACAGCUCGACAAACCUGACAAGGGGCUCAACGUGCAAGAACAGCUGGAACACACCCGGAACUGCCUGCUGAAAAUCGGAGACCGGAUAGCCGAGUGCCUUAAAGCCUACUCAGAUCAGGAGCACAUCAAACUCUGGAGGAGGAACCUAUGGAUUUUUGUUUCCAAGUUUACAGAAUUUGAUGCUCGAAAACUGCAUAAGUUAUACAAGAUGGCUCAUAAGAAAAGGUCUCAAGAAGAAGAGGAGCAAAAGAAGAAAGACGACGUGACUGGGGGUAAGAAACCAUUUCGUCCAGAGGCCUCAGGCUCCAGCCGGGACUCUCUGAUAUCUCAGUCCCAUACCUCACACAACCUUCACCCUCAGAAGCCUCAUUUGCCUGCCUCCCAUGGCCCACAGAUGCAUGGACACCCAAGAGAUAACUACAAUCACCCCAACAAGAGACACUUCAGUAAUGCAGAUCGAGGAGACUGGCAGAGGGAAAGAAAGUUCAACUAUGGUGGUGGCAACAACAAUCCACCAUGGGGAAGCGACAGGCACCAUCAGUAUGAGCAGCACUGGUACAAGGACCACCAUUAUGGGGACCGGCGACAUAUGGAUGCCCACCGUUCCGGAAGCUAUCGACCCAACAACAUGUCCAGAAAGAGGCCUUAUGACCAGUACAGCAGUGACCGAGACCACCGGGGACACAGAGAUUAUUAUGACAGGCACCAUCAUGACUCCAAGCGGAGGAGAUCCGAUGAAUUUAGGCCUCAAAAUUACCACCAGCAGGAUUUCCGACGAAUGUCUGAUCACCGCCCCGCUAUGGGCUACCAUGGCCAGGGACCCUCAGACCAUUACCGCUCUUUCCACACAGAUAAACUGGGGGAAUAUAAACAGCCUCUACCCCCAUUGCACCCUGCAGUCUCAGAUCCUCGCUCACCCCCUUCUCAGAAAUCUCCUCACGAUUCCAAGUCACCCCUGGAUCAUAGGUCUCCUUUGGAGAGAUCACUAGAACAGAAAAACAACCCAGAUUAUAACUGGAAUGUUCGGAAAACAUAAAGGACAGCUCGUAAAGGAGAGAGUAAGAGUCACCAAACACGUGGAUAUUUUUGGUCUGAUCCUACAGUAGCCGGUUAUCUAGACCAGUAAGUGGAGUUUUGGACAUGCUGCUGCUGUCAACUCACUGGCUGAAGGAGCACUUCAAGGAAUGGGAGGCCUUUCACUGGGUCCAGCUCUGAUUCGGGUCACCACUCCUGCACUUUGGCACCCCAUCCCAUUCCAGCCUAGUUCUGGCCUCCCACUUUGACGGGCACUUGGAGGAGGAGCUGACUGUGUGUGUACCAGCUUCACUGGGAUGUGUUUCCCCAGUCAAGGAACAGGGGAUCUUCAGAGUCAUGAAUGUUUUCUUGCCAGGGUCAGUGUUCCCAGGACCUUAGUGCAUGGUCGGGGCAGGAACUGGUGCAUGGAGGCUGCUGGGACCUGGUGAACAGUGUGUGAUUUGGUUGAUUUGGUUCACUCUGACAUGAUGGAUGCUGCUGAUGGGGAGUGGCGAGUUGGGGCAAGCGGGUGGGGACAAGCAUAGGACUUGAAGGGGAGCAGGUACACCCCUCAAAUGUGUUCUUGGGAGAAGUGAUACACUCGGCCUCAUUAUGUGAAACCUGUGGGUGGGGUUGGGGUGGAGAAGUAGAGAGAGGGCAACAGCUUCCACAACUGCUUCAUCUCUGCCAACACUAAUUUUUCCCACACUGUCUUUGUACAUUUCAGAGCUUUGGUCUCCUGAGUGGGCCUCCUUUUCCCACUGUGCCAGGGAAGGUAGGUUUCUCUGGCUGACUGAGUACUGUGAGUGAGGCAACACUGAUGCCAGCAUGGGUCUUACUUGACUGGGGAGUAGGCUGAGUGAGGGGUAGGGUGGGGUAGGUGGGGAGUAGUGUGGCCAGGGAACUGGAAUCCCUGGUGGAUUUCUGAUUCCUGUGGUGAGAAGGAAAGCUACAGGACCUGGAGAAGGGGAUGCAGAGGCAGGCCUGCUGACCAACUUGUUGCAAUCACAAAGGUGGGGGUCCUGGUGCAGGCAGUGAACAGGCUUCUAAUGUGGGGUUCAGUAGUGCCAGCAAGUGGGGGAAACUUUCAGUAUUGCGCUAGGUCAACACUUCCUGCUGCAUUUCCUUCCCUUUGCACAGCUUGAAGAAAUAGAGUAGACAGAAUCACACAUCAUGUGGUGGGCAGAUGGAAAUAAGUACCUGUGGUGAACAAGUUUCUACUGUAGUUGGAGAUCAUUAGAAUUGAAUUCAGUUUCUCUUAGAAUAUAAUCAGGUAUAAACCUAAGUUAAACUUUUUCCCAAACAAGGAGCAUCCAAAGACACAGUGACUUGAGCUAUAGAUAGUAAAAAUCAUACGAGAGUUGAACUGAGUCAGGUUUAGGAAGCAAGUUUGGUUGCAUCAAUUAAGCAGGCUCUUUUCAAUUGACUGAUGCUGGGGCCUUCAGUUUUAUUCUCAGUAUAGAUUGCCAGUAUUGUUAAGAGUAUCCAAAGGCCUUUCUAGAUGGAGACAGAAUAACUGACUUGAACAUACAGUGUGCCUGUAAGUGUCCAGGCUCAGAGCUGGUGAAAACCCUUCUGUUGGGCGUGUGCAGGGUUAAACUCCUGAAGUAACUUGUGAGGACUUCAGUGCUUGCUGGUGUCCUGGGCAGCACCAUGAAUGCCUUUACCAAGACAUGCCAAGUUGGAUCCCCCGAAUGAAGCAGAUGUGGCUGUGGUGUGACCCUUGCUCCCUGCUACACAGAGCAUCGCAGGGCUGGCCUGUGUGGUUUCCAGAUGAGGGUCUGGGUCCCGGAAGCUUGUGUUGAGAGCUCAGUGGACCCACCCCGCUUGCUGAACCCUCACAGUUCUUGGGGUUGUCCAGCCUGGACUUGUAGCACACAUGUCCUGAAGCAAAGCUCCGGUGACUGCAUGAGCCACCUGGCCACAGUCCUCCCAUGGAGGGCCUGCCGUGACGCUCAGUGGAGAGGGCAGGGCCUGUGUCUCCACUUAGGCCACACAGUGAUGAGGAAACCACAGAUGGAGCUUCUUGCCGAUAAUACUGACUCUAGCCCAUGAUUGCCUUGCCCAAGCCAAAGAGGAAGGUUAGGUUGGCUUGUCGAGCCCUUGAGCGUUGGGAGAUGGGGUGGGAAGGAGGUGAGCCCCUGCAGAGAGUUGGGUAGUGUCCUUCAGGAAUGAAAGGAGGGGCAAAGGAGUCACCAGAGGUCCUGCAUUUCCAUCAGGGUUUCCACAGUCAUCAGGGCUUCUCUCUUGAGUUGCUGAUAGGAGAUGUGAGUUAUGCCCAGAGAUGUCUUAUCGUGAGGAAAAAGAAACUUCCUUUUGUUCACAUUUAGGACUCUCAGUGCCAUAUGAAGUAGCAAAAGGCAGUAUCGGCCAGAUCAGUGUUACAUUGAUUCUAAAAUUACAGUGUCCCCAUUAGACAACUAUUUUAGGUGCUGGAGUAUGUUUGAAGAGUGUGCUGGGAAAAAGGAAGCAUUUCUUCAUUGAUUUAAAUCAGUAUGAAUAUUAUAUGCCUAAAUAAAAAAUUUGCACAGGUAAAUUCUCUCACUUGUGAAUGGGAGAAGCUGCCCCAGGAAUCUGUGAGGAUGGUAUUCCCUGGAGUCUGGCUUUGAAAGAUUUCAUUGUUGGUAGAAAUAACAGGUUGAGAAAGAGGGAGUUAGCAUCACCUAAAACCUGCACGUGAACAAGGGUUGACAUGAUACACUAUGGCCUUAGAAAAGGGCCAGGUGAAACCCCAAGCUAAUCACUGCGGUCUUUCAGAGCCGGACAGACAGGUGCCAGCAGAGCCCGGGGCUCACUCUCCUUUCAGUCAUUCCUCAGCCCUUCGAAGGGAAGCCCAAACACUUUGCACGCUGUGCUGCAGACAUUCUGGCCUGGUGUGUCUGAAAGUUGCAUCAGUCCUCACGGUGCAAACACAGUUGAUUUAGGAAGUCACACAAUGACACUGAAAUCCUACAGACCAAAAUCCACUUGUCAGCAGGAGCAGCAGCCCAGGCCCAGCACCAGCGGUCUUCCGGCUCCUCUGAGGGCUGCCACGUUGGGCGAGGGGAGCCAUGCCAAGGGUCCAGGCUGCUUUAGGCCAUCUGUGCCCCACUCAUCUGGGGACAGAUGGUUUUUCUUUAUUGUAAAAUUGUGGACUUUUAAAACCUGUUGACUAAACAGUAAUUAAUUUAUAUUUGUGAAAAAUGCCACUGUCCUAGUGAUUUCUGAUGUAAAUAAUGUUGUUUAUAUAGUAUGUAUUAAAUUUUCCUACAUUGUAAAACUGCUGUACUUUUGAUUCUUGUAUAUUAAAAAGUGUUACUGAGCAUUUUUAGAA